GCGCAUGCAGCCCUUCCCAAGCACUGGUAGGGCACUGGGCAUGCAGACAGCCCACCAGAAGGGAAGAAUCAGGAGAAAAGGGAUGCAAGAUCCCAGAGAUAAACUGAAGCACAAGAGGGUAAAAACUUUGUCCUUGGUCUUACAGCCAGAAAGUGGUGAUGCAAAGAACUUAGUCCAAGCUUUGAUCUGUUCUGCACUGCCUGCCAAAGCAGAACCUUGAGAAAUACCCAUGUUUGGGGGAUGAGAAGAAGAAGAUAAAUCAGCAAAGAAAAUAGUGAUAAGAAAGAUGCAGAACCCAGGGAUAUGGAGAGCCAAUUGUAUUUGUAAAACACUUAGAAUGGUGCCUGACACGUGAGUUGCUUUGUCUAAUUCUAGCCCUGUGGUAGCUACCCAAGAUUGUUGUAACCUCCAGUGAUCAAGUUCUUUGGAUAAGCAAAGAGGGAGGGCAUUAAGUGUGUGGAAAAGACCCCUCCUCUCCACUCUUGUUGCAAGGACUCAGGAUCCUGCCCUCUGAGGGUUUACAGAAGUCAUUCUCACUAUCUCACACUGGCCGUCUUGACCCAGAGCAGUUCUUUACUUUCUCGGGACACAAACGGGAUGAAAGUCCAGGGCUGGGACUUCCUCCUUGGAAUGUUUGACAAGGACUGACGUACUCUAGGCCCUUUGAAUCCCGGAAGUCCAGGACACACCCAACCUUGAUUACAGUGUCCAGAAUGCUGGAGCGUAGGUGAAAGGACAAAAGCCAGACACAUUUCAACAUGAGGGACCCACUGACAGAUUGUCCGUAUAAUAAAGUAUACAAGAACCUAAAGGAGUUUUCUCAAAAUGGAGAGAAUUUCUGCAAACAGGUCACAUCUGUUCUUCAGCAAAGGGCAAACCUGGAAAUUAGCUAUGCCAAAGGACUUCAGAAACUGGCAAGCAAGCUGAGCAAAGCAUUACAGAACACGAGAAAAAGUUGUGUUAGCAGUGCCUGGGCCUGGGCCUCAGAGGGAAUGAAAUCCACAGCGGACCUGCAUCAAAAACUUGGCAAAGCAAUUGAAUUGGAAGCAAUAAAACCGACUUAUCAAGUCCUAAAUGUACAAGAGAAGAAGAGAAAAUCACUUGACAAUGAAGUUGAAAAGACAGCAAAUCUUGUCAUUAGCAACUGGAAUCAGCAAAUUAAGGCCAAGAAGAAAUUAAUGGUUAGUACCAAGAAACAUGAAGCACUUUUCCAGCUUGUAGAAAGCUCCAAGCAAUCUAUGACUGAGAAGGAGAAGCGGAAGCUCCUCAAUAAACUGACAAAAUCAACUGAAAAGUUGGAAAAGGAAGAUGAAAAUUACUACCAAAAAAACAUGGCGGGUUAUUCUACCAGACUGAAAUGGGAAAACACACUAGAGAACUGCUACCAGGUAACCCACAGCAUCUGCCUAUAUGCCUUUUGGGUCAAAAGAGCCUGGGGAAAGUGUGUGAGUGAUUUAAGAUACCAAGACACAUUCCUUCCUGGAAAUCUCCCUCCACUAUGGUUUGGAUAUGACAUAGUCAAGAGGCUAAUCAUGAGACUUUGUUCAGUCUGUCUUCAGAGCAUUCUGGAGCUGGAGAAGGAAAGAAUUCAACUUUUAUGCAAUAACUUAAACCAGUACAGCCAACAUAUUUCUCUUUUUGGCCAAACCCUGACCACAUGCCACACGCAGAUUCACUGUGCCAUCAGCAAGAUUGACAUUGAAAAAGAUAUCCAGGCUGUAAUGGAAGAAACUGCAAUUUUAUCUACAGAAAACAAAUCUGAGUUCCUGUUAACGGAUUACUUUGAAGAAGAUCCUAACAGUGCAAUGGAUAAAGAGAGACGAAAGUCUUUACUAAAACCAAAAUUAUUGAGACUGCAGAGAGACAUUGAAAAAGCCUCAAAAGACAAGGAAGGCCUGGAACGAAUGCUUAAAACGUACUCCAGCACCUCCUCCUUCUCUGAUGCAAAGAGCCAGAAAGACACAGCAGCGUUAAUGGAUGAGAACAAUUUGAAACUAGACCUUUUGGAAGCGAACUCCUACAAACUGUCAUCAAUGUUAGCAGAACUUGAGCAAAGACCUCAACCCAGCCAUCCUUGUAGUAAUUCCAUCUUCAGGUGGAGGGAAAAGGAGCAUACUCAUAGCUAUGUGAAAAUAUCUCGGCCUUUUUUAAUGAAGAGAUUAGAGAAUAUUGUGAGCAAGGCAUCUUCUGGUGGGCAGAGCAAUCCAGGUUCUUCAACUCCAGCCCCUGGUGCAGCCCAGCUCAGCAGCAGACUUUGCAAGGCCUUGUAUUCUUUUCAAGCCAGGCAAGAUGAUGAGUUGAAUUUGGAAAAGGGUGACAUUGUGAUUAUACACGAGAAAAAAGAAGGAGGAUGGUGGUUUGGAUCUUUGAAUGGGAAAAAAGGCCAUUUUCCUGCCGCUUAUGUGGAGGAGUUACCUUCAAAUGCUGGCAACACAGCUACAAAGGCAUAAAACAAGACUCUGAACAUACUACCUUCACACUCGGUAAUCAACAAUACAGUGUGGUUCAAAUAAGAAUAAAGUGCUCUUACCUUUACAUGUUUUUCUUUUGAAAUGGAUGGAGUUCUACCUGCAUGUCACAGCACUUUGCAUUCAUGAUUAUUAGCUUGAAACAGUCAGAAAAAAGAUGGAUGGGUGGAGACAGACAAGGAAGAGGCUCCUUGGUUCCUAGAGGAGUUUCCAAAUUCUAGGAGACCCUAGAGAUGAUCCAGUAUAACCCCUGGUGUCACAGAAACAGACGGAGUCCAAGGUGGGUUCAGCUGCUUGCCUGAAGUCAGAGUUAUCUGGUAGACAACAGCAGUGGGACUUAGAUGUCUUUUUCCUCUGGAUUUGGGUGGCAACAGAACACAGCAGGCCUAUGAGGGGGUCAAGCAGAGCCUGGGAGAUGAGGAACACAGAUCAAUUCCAAGAAGAGAGACAGGCAAUCAAGACACCAAUGAGAUCAACCCAAAUUAGGGGAUGGUAGGAUAUCUCUGACAAACCCACAGCCAAUAUC